ACAGUCGCAGCCCCGGCGCCCCGAAGCGGGAAAAAGGCUGGGUGCCGCCGUCCCCCAGCUGCGCAACCCUAGGAACUCUCGGGUUCACAGUCUCUCUUUUUCUAGGAACUUGGCUGUGUUGUCCUGCCUCAGAGACAAAUUCAUCUAUUGUAGGCCUAGCCCCUGCCUUUGAAAACAAGGAAAGGUUGGUAGAACAUCAACACAGCAUGGAAUUUCCAGGGAGGUCUCAUUUCAAAACUUCAUAAAGAACAAGAACCACCUGGACUUCUGUGAGGGCGAUGAUUAAACUGGCCUGAGUUUGAAUGAAAGGAUAAUGUAUGCUCAACCUGUGACUAACACCAAGGAGGUCAAGUGGCAGAAGGUCUUGUAUGAGCGACAGCCCUUUCCUGAUAACUAUGUGGACCGGCGAUUCCUGGAAGAGCUCCGGAAAAACAUCCAUGCUCGGAAAUACCAAUAUUGGGCUGUGGUAUUUGAGUCCAGUGUGGUGAUCCAGCAGCUGUGCAGUGUUUGUGUUUUUGUGGUUAUCUGGUGGUAUAUGGAUGAGGGUCUUCUGGCCCCCCAUUGGCUUUUAGGGACUGGUCUGGCUUCUUCACUGAUUGGGUAUGUUUUGUUUGAUCUCAUUGAUGGAGGUGAAGGGCGGAAGAAGAGUGGGCAGACCCGGUGGGCUGACCUGAAGAGUGCCCUAGUCUUCAUUACUUUCACUUAUGGGUUUUCACCAGUGCUGAAGACCCUUACAGAGUCUGUCAGCACUGACACCAUCUAUGCCAUGUCAGUCUUCAUGCUGUUAGGCCAUCUCAUCUUUUUUGACUAUGGUGCCAAUGCUGCCAUUGUAUCCAGCACACUAUCCUUGAACAUGGCCAUCUUUGCUUCUGUAUGCUUGGCAUCACGUCUUCCCCGGUCCCUGCAUGCCUUCAUCAUGGUGACAUUUGCCAUUCAGAUUUUUGCCCUGUGGCCCAUGUUGCAGAAGAAACUAAAGGCAUGUACUCCCCGGAGCUAUGUGGGGGUCACACUGCUUUUUGCAUUUUCAGCCGUGGGAGGCCUACUGUCCAUUAGUGCUGUGGGAGCCGUACUCUUUGCCCUUCUGCUGAUGUCUAUCUCAUGUCUGUGUCCAUUCUACCUCAUUCGCUUGCAGCUUUUUAAAGAAAACAUUCAUGGGCCUUGGGAUGAAGCUGAAAUCAAGGAAGACUUGUCCAGGUUCCUCAGUUAAAUUAGGACAUCCAUUACAUUAUUAAAGCAAGCUGAUAGAUUAGCCUCCUAACUAGUAUAGAACUUAAAGACAGAGUUCCAUUCUGGAAGCAGCAUGUCAUUGUGGUAAGAGAAUAGAGAUCAAAACCAAAAAAAAUGAACCAAAGGCUUGGGUGGUGAGGGUGCUUAUCCUUUCUGUUAUUUUGUAGAUGAAAAAACUUUCUGGGGACCUCUUGAAUUACAUGCUGUAACAUAUGAAGUGAUGUGGUUUCUAUUAAAAAAAUAACACAUCCA